UUUUUUUUUUUUUUGAGAUGGAAUCUUGCUCUGUCACUCAGACUGGAGGCAGUGGCACGACCUUGGCUCACAGCAACCUCCACCUCCCAGGUUCAAGUGAUUCUCCCGCCUCAGCCUCCCGAAUAGCUGGGAUUACAGGCACCCGCCGCCACACCCAGGUGAUUUUUGUAUUUUUGUAGAGACAGGGUUUCACCAUGUUAGCUAGGCUGAUCUUGAACUCCUGACCUCAGGUAAUCCGCCGGCCUCAGCUUCCCAAAGUGCUGGGAUUACACAUGUGAGCCACAGCACCCAGCCAAUUUUGAGUUUUUUCUAUGUGCUCUUUCUCAUUUAUCAUUACCUGGAAAGUUUGAGGUACUUAUUCUUAGCAUAAUACAUUUUCUUUUUUCUUCAAGACUCAGACUAGAGAAACACAGCUGAAUAUUCUAAAUUCAAUGAAAUCAACUCUUUAAAAUCAUUACAUGUGGUCUGAAUCCAAAUCAGACAAGAUCUAAAGAAAAUCAAACAGUGCAUAAUUCUCUUUAAGUCUUCUUGGGUUUGUACGUGUGUUAAGAAUGGGGAAAUGAGAGUGGCUUCUGGUGCUCUGGGGUGAGCUCUGCCUGGCUGCAGGGAUGGCGGGGAGAAGGAAGCUCAUCGCAGUGAUCAGAGACAAGGACACGGUGACUGGUUUCCUGCUGGGCAGCAUAGGGGAGCUUAACAAGAACUGCCACCCCAAUUUCCUGGUGGUGGAGAAGGAUACGACCAUCAAUGAGAUCGAAGACACUUUCCGGCAAUUUCUAAACCGGGAUGACACUGGCAUCAUCCUCAUCAACCAGUACAUCGCAGAGAUGGUGCAGCAUGCCCUGGACACCCACCAGCACUCUAUCCCUACUGUCCUGGAGAUCCCCUCCAAGGAGCACCCAUAUGAGGACGCCAAGGACUCCACCCUGCGGAGGGCCAGGGGCAUGUUCACUGCCGAAGACCUGUGCUAGGGUCUUUGUGUGAGGACUCCUCACAGCCCUCAGCCCUUCCCUCAUUCUCAGGCCUCUCCCCAGGCUUGCCAUCAGCCUUCUUUACAUUUUGAGCCUCUAAUUUCCAAGUCCCUGCCCCUUCCCACUCCAUUAAGAGGCUAGGUGAGGCGCUUCUAGGUUGCUGGGGCUCUGCUGUUAAAAUCAAGGCUGGUUAAGGAACAGGAAGCCUGACCAUCUCUCUCCACUACCUCUUCCCUGUGCUGUUACACAGUGUCAUUGUUGAUGUUAAAUUACAGUCAUAUUCUUGCUUCUCUCAAAAAAAAAAAAAAAAAAAAAAAAAGAAUGGGGAAAUGAGCAAGGACUUAGAAUUUUAGGAACAGGCUUAUUUUCUUAGGAUGAGUGGAUGCAGCUAGGAAAAGAUGGCAAGGGCAGUGCAAUUGUUUGGUAAAGACAUGAUGGAUUCUCCACAAUGUCUUCUGUAUUUGUGUUUCCCAGAGUAUGCGUGCGCCUAUGCAUGUUUUUUUUAACAUAAAAGAUUACUCUUCUAAAGAAACAGUACAAGGGCAUCCUGCAAUGACAGAAAGCAAGGGUGUUACCCAAAAUUCAUGAGUUAAGGUCAAACAGACAGAAGCAAGCUUAAAGGGCUUCCACUAGCCAAAUUUCUGAGAAUGUGAGCAUUAAAAGUAUAACAAUUAUAGUGGAUUACAAAAUACUGAAUCCAUAAUGACACUAAAAAAGGAACAGACAAAUUCAUUUGAAACAUAUGAAGUGUCUAUUUUACAAAAACCUUGCUUUGAAAACUGGUAAUGAAAAAGAAAAAUCUAAUCAUGUAUCAGGCCUUUCCCAUAGGAAACACAUUUCAGGGACUCUAAUAGCCCCAGCUAAGGAAAAAUGCAAUCAGAAUGCCAAUUAAGAAGUGUAAAAGUGAUAAAAUUAGAAAAAUAUUAUUUCAUUAACUCUAAUAAAACUAUUAUCAGGUAUUAGCAAAUGAUAUUAAUUAUUAGGUGAUGGCUGAUGUGAAAUUCAUCAUUCAUAUAACGCCAAAGUAACAUUAUUUAGAUUACAUUCAAGUCACACGGGAAAAAACCUAACUGUACAAUUAACCACCAGACUGUCAGUUCCUCAAUCCAGAGGUCAGUCUAGCAUCAUGAAUAAUAGGAGAACCAAAACAAGAUACUGUUUGUUUUUCAAAUGUGAUAAAUGCAGCACACCUUUUAGUCACAUCUAAAACCUAGCUUAUAAAAAAUACAGGUGAUUUUUUGACAAAAUAAUGAUACCACGAGGAAGCAACCUGCCAAAUCCAAAAAGUAGAACAUUAUACAGAAAAGUCAUGUCAUUUAAAAAAAGGAGGCUGAGGCUGGGCAUGGUGGCUCAUGCCUAUAAUCCCAGGAAGGGAUCGGGAGGCCAAGGAAGGCAGAUCACAAGGUCUGGAGUUCGAGACUAGCCUUGCUAAUAUGGCGAAAUGCCGUCUCUACUAAAAAUACAAAAAUUAGCAGGACAUGGUGGCGGGCACCUGUAGUCCCAGCUACUCGGAAGGCUGAGGCAGGAGAAUUGCUUGAACCUGGGAGGCGGAGGUUGCAGUGAGCCGAGAUCACACCACUGCAUUCCAGCCUGGCCGACAGAGCAAGGCUCCGUCUCAACAAAACAAAAAAACAAAACAAAACAAAACAAAACAAAACAAAAAAAGGCUGUUCUAGUUAUAAGUGACAAAGCCAAUAACUUCCAGAUGCAAAACUAAACUAACUAUAAAAGAUACUUUUGGGUCAACUGAGA